GAUGUCAUCCUGAGCAGCUGGGCGGCGGGUGCCGGUGCGCACGGAGCCGAGCCGGGGCUCCCGUUGCGCUGCACCGCGUUGGGUCGGAGUCCCAGGACUUCAGCGGAGAUCCGCGCGCUGCGACGGCCGGUGCAGAGCCCGCCGAGCGCCCAGUCCCGGCCCGGGGCUGAGUUGGGGGCAUGCUCUAGCCGCCCCCCCGGAGCCCGGGAGAGAACCCAGGAGCGCCGCCGCCCAGCCCCAGCGCCCCGAGCGGAACCGCUGCGAAGGGGCCCUGAACGGCCGUCGCCCUCCCUACGGGCAGCCCCCGGGGGUUGGCGACCGAAGUCUAGGUUUUCGAGAAGUGAGUGUCCCCCACCCCAUGAGGUUUGGGGGGCCAGGAAGGAGGAGCUGAGGUGGGGGAGGGUGCCAGGUUCUAGGAGCGGGGUGGCAUCGGGACAGCACCUCCAGUCUUGGGGUUGUCCCAAGUGGCCGGGAUUAGUGGAGCAGCGAUGCGUUCCAUUCUGAAAGGGGCAGGGAUGACGAUCGGGGCUCCAUUCUGAGUCGGGGCUGGCUUGGGGGAUAGGCCCUAUUCUGGGAGGGGUUGUUUUGGAGGCUUUCUGUCUGAGAGAAGGGAGGGACAUGUCCAGGAUGGGAGGGGGCUGCACCCCUAUUUUAGGGUCUGGGCAAGGAUAGGAGGGAAAAGACCUGGGCACUCCACGCAGCCUCCCGGCUCUCCUGAGGAACUGAUGGGCUUUCUCUGUCUCUUUCUUGCUGAUCUUUCUGCCUGACUUCGUUUUCAAAAGAGCCAGGGUGGGAACCCUAACUGGACUCUUCGGGACCCCCAGGAAGGAUCUGAGGCCUGAGCCAUCCUCCUUUCUACCCUGUCUGCCCCCCAGGACUGGGCAGUUGCAGGAGGCCCUGGGGGGGGGCCCAGGACUGUGGUUGUGCCCCCCCCCCAAAGGCCGGACAGGAUGGGACCAAGUUAGUCUGUCCAGUCUCACCCAGCACCUCCCAGGCCCAGAGAGAACCCCCGGGGCUCUGAAAGCUUGCCCUGCCGCCUGACCGCCAUGGAGACGAAGCUGCCCCCUGCAAGCACCCCCACUAGCCCCUCCUCCCCCGGGCUGUCGCCUGUGCCCCCACCCGACAAGGUGGACGGCUUCUCCCGCCGUUCCCUCCGCAGAGCCCGGCCCCGCCGCUCCCACAGCUCCUCUCAGUUCCGCUAUCAGAGCAACCAGCAAGAGCUCACACCGCUGCCCCUGCUCAAAGAUGUGCCGGCUUCCGAGCUGCACGAGCUGCUGAGCCGGAAGCUGGCCCAGUGUGGGGUGAUGUUUGACUUCUUGGACUGUGUGGCCGACCUCAAGGGGAAGGAGGUGAAGCGGGCAGCCCUCAACGAGCUGGUGGAGUGUGUGGGGAGCACCCGGGGUGUCCUCAUCGAGCCCGUCUACCCAGACAUCAUCCGCAUGAUCUCAGUGAAUAUCUUCCGGACUCUGCCGCCCAGUGAGAACCCUGAAUUUGACCCUGAAGAGGAUGAGCCCAAUCUUGAGCCUUCGUGGCCACACCUGCAGCUGGUAUAUGAGUUUUUCCUGCGUUUCUUGGAGAGCCCAGACUUCCAGCCCUCCGUGGCCAAGAGAUAUGUGGAUCAAAAGUUUGUCCUGAUGCUCCUGGAGCUAUUUGAUAGUGAGGAUCCCCGGGAGCGUGAGUACCUCAAGACCAUCCUGCACCGGGUCUAUGGCAAGUUCCUGGGUCUCCGGGCCUACAUCCGCAAACAGUGCAACCACAUCUUCCUCCGGUUCAUCUAUGAAUUCGAGCACUUCAAUGGUGUGGCUGAGCUGCUGGAGAUCCUAGGAAGCAUCAUCAAUGGCUUUGCGCUGCCCCUGAAGACGGAGCACAAGCAGUUCCUGGUUCGCGUCCUGAUCCCCCUGCACUCUGUCAAGUCGCUGUCUGUCUUCCAUGCCCAGCUGGCAUACUGUGUGGUGCAGUUCCUGGAGAAGGAUGCCACUCUGACAGAGCACGUGAUCCGGGGGCUGCUCAAAUACUGGCCAAAAACCUGCACCCAGAAGGAGGUGAUGUUUCUGGGGGAGAUGGAAGAGAUUCUUGAUGUCAUCGAGCCCUCCCAGUUUGUGAAGAUCCAGGAGCCCCUUUUUAAGCAGGUGGCUCGCUGUGUUUCCAGCCCCCAUUUCCAGGUUGCAGAGCGGGCUCUGUAUUUCUGGAACAAUGAGUAUAUCCUAAGCCUCAUUGAGGACAACUGCCACACUGUGCUGCCUGCUGUGUUUGGGACCCUCUACCAAGUCUCCAAGGAGCACUGGAACCAAACCAUCGUAUCACUGAUCUACAAUGUGCUCAAGACCUUCAUGGAGAUGAAUGGGAAGCUGUUUGAUGAGCUCACAGCCUCCUACAAGCUGGAAAAGCAGCAGGAGCAGCAGAAGGCCCAGGAGCGUCAGGAGUUAUGGCAAGGUCUGGAGGAGCUGCGGCUACGCCGGCUACAGGGGACCCAGGGGGCCAAGGAGGCCCCCCUCCAGCGGCUUACACCCCAGGUGGCCGCCAGUGGGGGUCAGAGCUAGACAGCACCUCAGAAGGGGAAAAGCUAAACCCAGAGCUGUCAGUCCCUCUAUCCCUUCUCCUGUCCAGGGGCCCAGAGAGAAACACACCUACCCCUGGCCUUGCCAGAGUGGCUUCUGAGGACUCCCUGCCCAGCCCAGCUUUCACUGGGGGGAGACGAGGAGAGGCAAUGGUGGUCUUGGCAACAGAAUGCUCAGCCCCUCGUGGCAGGACUUGACAAGGGCAAGCUUGACCAGGAAGCUGCCAUCAGGGAUCUUCCCCUGCCCCGCAAAGCUAGGCUCCAGCUGCAGGCGGGCUCCCACCCUCUGCUCCUGGCCUUGGGCAAGGGCACUCAGCGCCUCGCCUGCCCCUGCCUUGGCCAAUGCGAGGUCCUUCCUUAUCCCCACCAUGGGGUCCAUGGUCUAUUUAUUCUCGCCCAGCUCACCCUCUACACAGACACUGUCCUGGGUGCACACUCCUCCCUUCCCUCGCUGUGUACUUCCUUGUCCCCUUUUUAUUUAUUGGGCAGGGGGAGGGGGAGGGCACAGGCAAGAAGAGAUUCACAGUGUCCUGGGGUAAGGGGGGGUUCACAGUAAUCAUGGUCUACUCCUCUUUCCGUGGCUGGGGGUAGACUUAAUAAAGAGAGAAAUUCAA